CGGUUGCGCGUGGCGCACGGGGUGGGAGCGGAGCCCAGGCCGGGAGCAGGCGCCGCCGCCACAGGCGACCAUGGGGAACGUGUUGGCUGCCAGCUCGCCGCCCGCAGGGCCGCCACCGCCGCCUGCGCCGGCCCUCGUGGGGCUGCCGCCACCUCCGCCCUCGCCGCCGGGCUUCACGCUGCCGCCGCUGGGAGGCAGCCUGGGCGCCGGCACCAGUACGAGUCGAAGUUCGGAACGGACCCCCGGGGCUGCAACCGCCAGCGCCUCAGGGGCCGCCGAGGAUGGGGCCUGCGGCUGCCUGCCCAACCCGGGCACAUUCGAGGAGUGCCACCGGAAGUGCAAGGAGCUGUUUCCCAUUCAGAUGGAGGGUGUCAAGCUCACAGUCAACAAAGGGUUGAGUAACCAUUUUCAGGUCAACCACACAGUAGCCCUCAGCACAAUCGGGGAGUCCAACUACCACUUCGGGGUCACAUAUGUGGGGACAAAGCAGCUGAGUCCCACAGAGGCGUUCCCUGUACUGGUGGGUGACAUGGACAACAGUGGCAGUCUCAACGCUCAGGUCAUUCACCAGCUGGGCCCCGGUCUCAGGUCCAAGAUGGCCAUCCAGACCCAGCAGUCGAAGUUUGUGAACUGGCAGGUGGACGGGGAGUAUCGGGGCUCUGACUUCACAGCAGCCGUCACCCUGGGGAACCCAGACGUCCUCGUGGGUUCAGGAAUCCUCGUAGCCCACUACCUCCAGAGCAUCACGCCUUGCCUGGCCCUGGGUGGAGAGCUGGUCUACCACCGGCGGCCUGGAGAGGAGGGCACUGUCAUGUCUCUAGCUGGGAAAUACACAUUGAACAACUGGUUGGCAACGGUAACGUUGGGCCAGGCGGGCAUGCACGCAACAUACUACCACAAAGCCAGUGACCAGCUGCAGGUGGGUGUGGAGUUUGAGGCCAGCACAAGGAUGCAGGACACCAGCGUCUCCUUCGGGUACCAGCUGGACCUGCCCAAGGCCAACCUCCUCUUCAAAGGUGCUGGAGGACAGUGUGCUGCCACCCUGUGGGCCUCCACAUUACCAGGGAACACUUGUUAAAAGGUAGGUGGGGCCGGGUGCGGUGGCUCACGCCUGUAAUCCCAGCACUUUGGGAGGCCAAGGCGGGCCGAGGUAAGGAGAUUGAGACCAUCCUGGCUAACACGGUGAAACUCCGUCUCUACUAAAAAUACAAAAACAAAAUUAGCCGGGUGUGGUUGCGGGUGCCUAUAGUCCCAACUACUGAGGCUGAGGCGGGAAAAUGGUAUGAACCCAGGAGGCGGAGCUUGCGGUGAGCCGAGAUCGUGCCACCGCACUCCAGCCUGGGUGACAGAGCAAGACUCCAUCUCAAAAAAAAAAAAGUAGGUGGACAACCCUCUACUAUGUUUUAUGCUUGGAAAAAAAAAGUAGGUAGAGCAGCCAGGCGUGGUGACUCACGCCUGUAAUCCCAGCAUUUUGGGAGGCCAAGCCAGGUAGAAUACUUGAGGCCAGGAGUUGGAGACCAGCCUGGCCAACGUGGUGAAAUCCCCUCUCUACUAAAAGUACAAAAAUUAGCCAGGUGUGGUAGCGUGCUGCAACUGUAGUCCCCGCUACUUAGGAGGCUGAGGCACAAGAAUCACUUGAACCUGGGAGGCGGAGGUUGCAGGGAGUUGAGACUGCACCACUGCACUCCAGCCUGGGUGACAGAGUGAGACUCCAUCUCCAAAAAAAAUAAAAUGAAAUAAAUAAAUAAAUGUUAAAAAAAAUCUGGUGGAGCAUCUGAUGGGUGUUUGGGCCAAGCUGGAGCUUUGUCCAUCCCCUCUUAUUUUUCUGCACUUGACUCUCUUAUUUUUCUGAGACUGGUCUCCCUCUGUCGCCCAGGCUAGAGUGCAGCAGUGCAACUGCGGCUCACUGCAGCCUCCACCUCCCGGGCUCAAGCAGCCUUCCCACCUCAGCCUCCUGAGUAGCUAGGACCACAGGUGUAUGCCACCAGGCCCAGCUAAUUUUUUUGAUAGUUUUGGGAGACAUGGGGGUUUCACCAUGUUGCCCAGGCUGGUCUCGAACUCCUGGACUCAAGCCUUGGCCUCCCAAAGUGCUGGGAUUAUAGGUGUGAGCCACCACACCCAGCCAGGGUAGAAGGCACUUUGGAAGCCUCGAGCCUGCCCCAUUCAUCUUACGUUAGUGGAAACUGAGGCUUCCAGAGGUUUCAAGGUCACAACUAAAUCCAGAACCUCAUCUCAGGCACACUGGUCGUAGUCCCAAUGUCCAGUCUUAAGUCUUCUUGGAUAUCUGUGGCUCACAGAUUUUGGGUGUUUGAGCCUCCUGCUGAGCACUGCUGGGGCCACAGCGGUGACCAGCCCUGUCUUCACGGGACUCAGUGAGAGGAACAGAUUCAUCCGCAGAGUGGGCAGGACUAGGUUGGGGGAACCCAGGGGUCUAGAGGGCUUUUCAGAGGGCAGGGGUCACUGAGCGGAGAGCAGAGGAGGAGUGAGCCAUUUGCUCCAGCGUGAAGUUGUUGGUGUGAUGGGGUUUCAGGGUGGCAGGAGCAGUGUGGUUAAAGGUCUGGAAGCUGUCGGCAUGUGGCUGGUAUCCAAGGUGGCCAGGAACUCUGCAUGGAUAUGGUGGGAAGCUGGCACGCCUCUCACCUCAGCUCUUCC